AGCUCAACCCCCAGCACGGCUGCAUCCACCAUGUCCGUCUGCUCCAGCGACCUGAGCUAUGGCAGCCGCGUCUGCCUUCCUGGUUCCUGUGACUCUUGCUCCGACUCCUGGCAGGUGGACGACUGCCCAGAGAGCUGCUGUGAGCCCCCCUGCUGCGCCCCGGCCCCCUGCCUGAGCCUGGUCUGCACCCCAGUGAGCCGUGUAUCCAGCCCCUGCUGCCGAGUGACCUGUGAGCCCAGCCCCUGCCAAUCAGGCUGCACCAGCUCCUGCACGCCCUCGUGCUGCCAGCAGUCUAGCUGCCAGCCGGCUUGCUGCACCUCCUCCCCCUGCCAGCAGGCCUGCUGCGUGCCCGUCUGCUGCAAGACUGUCUGCUGCAAGCCUGUGUGCUGUAUGCCCGUCUGCUGUGGGCCUUCUUCUUCAUGCUGCCAGCAGUCUAGCUGCCAGCCAGCUUGCUGCAUCUCCUCCCCGUGUCAACAGUCCUGCUGUGUGCCCGUCUGCUGCAAGCCCAUCUGCUGUGUGCCUGUCUGCUCUGGGGCCUCCUCUCUGUGCUGCCAGCAGUCUAGCUGCCAGCCAGCUUGCUGCACCACCUCCUGCUGCAGACCCUCCUCCUCCGUGUCCCUCCUCUGCCGCCCUGUGUGCAGACCCGCCCGCCGCGUGCCCGUCCCCUCCUGCUGUGUCCCCACCUCCUCCUGCCAGCCAAGCUGCGGCCGCCUGGCCUCCUGCGGGUCCCUCCUCUGCCGCCCCACAUGUUCCCGCCUGGCCUGCUGAGGCCUCUGCUCAGGCCAGAAGUCCAGCUGCUGCCAGGCAUGUCCCCCAGGGCCACUGGGCACUAUGAGUCCCCCACCUCUCCCACUACUGGCCCCUCGGCUGCUC